CUCCCCCUCGCCGACGGCCCAAGGCGUUCAGGCACGCGCUUUCGGUGCUCGGAGCGGAAGCAGCGGCGAGAGGCUCGGAGGCGCGGGGGCGGCCGAGCGGCGGGCGACGGGGGCGGGCGACGGGGGCGGGCGACGCGGGCCGCGGCACGGGCGGAGCCGGGGCCAUGGAGCCGCCGCUGCCGGGCUAGGCAGGUCGUGCCCCGCCGGGCCGGCGGCGAUGUCGGGCUACCAGCGCCGCCCGGGCGCCACCCCGCUGUCCCGAGCCCGGAGCCUCGCCAUUCCCGACGCUCCAGCGUUCUAUGAGCGCCGGUCUUGUCUCCCCCAGCUAAAUUGUGAGCGCCCCCAUGGCAGGGACCUGGACUCCCCCUUCUUCGGCAUUCGGCCGGCCUUUAUGUGCUAUGUGCCCAGCCCGGUGCUGGCUUCCGUGGGAGACACAGGUGAGAGACGAGGGCGCCGGCCCCGGGGACGCUUCCAGUUCCCGCGCCACGUGUGGCACCUCCGCUGCAGCACGAGCUCGUCCAUUGACCCAUCAAUGUGCAGAGCGCUCACUGCGUGCCAGGCACUCGGAAUUCAAAGGCGGAGUCCCCUGCUAGGAGCUCACAGUCUGGUUGCGGGGAGACCUCCCCCAAGACAGACAGUUCCAGUACAGGAUGAUGACAGAUUUGAAGAUCUGGAAGAGGCAAAUCCAUUCUCUUUUAGAGAGUUUCUGAAGACCAAGAACCUCGGCCUCUCGAAAGAGGAUCCGGCCAGCAGAAUUUAUGCAAAGGAAGCCUCGAGGCAUUCCCUGGGACUUGACCACAACUCCCCACCCUCCCAAACCGGCGGGUAUGGCCUGGAGUAUCAGCAGCCAUUUUUCGAGGAUCCGACAGGGGCUGGUGACCUCCUGGAUGAGGAGGAGGAUGAGGACACCGGAUGGAGUGGGGCCUACCUGCCGUCCGCCAUCGAGCAGACUCACCCCGAGAGGGUCCCUGCCGGCACGUCGCCCUGCAGCACAUACCUUUCCUUUUUCUCCACCCCGUCGGAGCUGGCAGGGCCUGAGUCUCUGCCCUCGUGGGCGUUGAGUGACACUGAUUCUCGCGUGUCUCCGGCCUCUCCGGCAGGGAGUCCUAGCGCAGACUUUGCGGUUCAUGGAGAGUCUCUGGGAGACAGGCACCUGCGGACGCUGCAGAUAAGUUACGACGCACUGAAAGAUGAAAAUUCUAAGCUGAGAAGAAAGCUGAAUGAGGUUCAGAGCUUCUCUGAAGCUCAAACAGAAAUGGUGAGGACGCUUGAGCGGAAGUUAGAAGCAAAAAUGAUCAAGGAGGAAAGCGACUACCACGACCUGGAGUCGGUGGUUCAGCAGGUGGAGCAGAACCUGGAGCUGAUGACCAAACGGGCUGUAAAGGCAGAAAACCACGUCGUGAAACUAAAACAGGAAAUCAGUUUGCUCCAGGCGCAGGUCUCCAACUUCCAGCGAGAGAAUGAAGCCCUGCGGUGCGGCCAGGGUGCCAGCCUGACCGUGGUGAAGCAGAACGCCGACGUGGCCCUGCAGAACCUCCGGGUGGUCAUGAACAGUGCACAGGCUUCCAUCAAGCAACUGGUUUCCGGAGCUGAGACACUGAAUCUUGUUGCCGAAAUCCUUAAAUCUAUAGACAGAAUUUCUGAAGUUAAAGACGAGGAGGAAGACUCUUGAGGACCCCUGGGUGUUCUCAGCAUGAAGCUCCGUGUAUACCCUGAGGUCACCACCGCUCGAUCUAAAUGUGCAGUUGUGUCCUUAAAUAUGCAGUCUUCACCCAGAGUAAAGUGUUGAUCGCAAGAGUCCAGUGUCGUGCCCUCAGCCAGUUCUUGGCCACCACAAUGGGAGCAGCCCUGGCCGAGUUGUCUCUGUGGUUUCUAUGCAGCCCUUCUUGGCGAAAUUCCUGCGAUCUUAUAGAUUCUAAUGAGCUCUUGGAAGACAUUGUCAUAAAAGCCAGUGAUUUUAAGAAAAAGAGUGGUUCUGGAAUCAAUGUUUUCCAGUCCCAUCCCAGAACAUCAGUUGUAAGAUAAGUACAAUUGGUUGUCCUUGAUUUCAUAAGUAGAACAAACACUAAAUGUGCCUCUGAGAUGGCCACCCCGGGCAGGGACCUGUGCCUUCCGCCGAUGCUCAGGGCUCCCUCUGGCUCCCGGGUCACUCUUGUGGCCCCAGUGGGUGGUCCCUGCAGUCAUGGCCUGAGUGCGCAGGGGCCACCGCGUGGCUGCUGCUGUCCUCCUCCGGGACCCACGGGGACCAAGGUCACACGUUCCGUGCUGUGAAGCUGUCCAGAUGUGCCUCUUUGGCUGGGGGUUCUGGUGGACGUUUCAAGUGGCAUUUUGUACAAUGCAGGUUAGAAUUCAGGAAUUUCAAGUAUGUGCCCGGGUCUGUCAGGUCCCAGUUGCCUUUCUGACGGCCCCCCUCAGAGGGACGGCGAUGAGCACUAAAUGCUUUUUUGACUAUUUUCCUAUAGAUUUUUUUUAAAACUUUUUUUUCCUCCUGUUCCAAUUGAUAGCUUUCUUAUUUAAUAAAUUCUGUAGUUCACCGCA